UCAAAUGGGCUUAAGUAAAAAGGGAUUUAUUGGCUCCAAACCUGGAAGGGGCUGAGGUAUCACUAAAUCCAGUGACUCCGGUGAUGUAUUUGUGUAUCUCUCCCUUUCUGCAAAGGGCCAGUAACCCCUCAGUUCCCUAUCUACUUUGCGACUAUAAUUGCAAGCCUCAUUCUGUCCUGUUACAGUCGUGCGGCAAUUAGGCUGAGGGACUGGCGCGCCCGCUCCCCCGACUGUGAGCCUAGGCGGCGGGUGUCAUGCCCCUCCCCACUCCCGGGCGGAACAGAAUAUUGGGACAUGUUGGUGAUUCUUAGCUGUAUCUCACUAUUCCAUUGACAUUUCAACCAGUGUGACACAAAAUGUCAGUUAUUUCAGCAAGACGCUUCCAGUUACUUCCUGCUCUUAAAAAAAAAAAAAAAAAAAGAAUAAAUCUCUCAUGACUCUAUAUCCUUCUUGACACCUAACCAAGAGAAAUUGAGAUGACAGUUAAUUGCAAAUUAAUAAAGAAGGCCAUCAUCUACUCAGCCUUUACCUAAGUGGAAUCCUGUCUUUUGCGCAUUUAACUUACAAGAAUUUACCUGCAUCAGUCAGUUAUGUGAAGAAGAAAAGGGAAUAUAUUUCAGCGUACACAAGGCCCUUGUGCUUUUUAGGAGGAGUUCUUUGGAGCUGAAGUGGGUCUGAGAAGAGACAUUCUCAUGAUAGUGGAGACAGUAUUAUAGAAGCUGGAAGUGAUCAUUUUUCUCUGUUAUUUAUUUCACUUAUUACCUCACACACAUAUUGAUAUAAAACUGAUCAAUAAAGUUAGAAUUUCUACAUUAUCUAGAUAUUUGUAGACUUCGUUCAUAUUAUUGUUUUGUAUAUUGUGAUAGGGGAUUAGAUUUUUCUUUUCUAGGCUGGAGCUGAUUGUCUGACAAUUCAUAGCAGUAACUUAGCACUCACUGUAUACAGGAAGGUCUUAGGCACUGUUCCUUCCCCUUACUUUUCUUUUUAACAUUUUUUAAUCUGUAUGUACUUAUGAUCACUCUCCUCAUUUAGACAUUCACCAACAACAGAAAGAGAAACAGAGGGUUGGGCUUUUUCGUCGUGGCAGUUCUGGCACUGUGAGCUACAAUUACCUAAAUGUGCCUUCUUGGAAAGAAAUUCCAGGGUCAAGUAAAGCAGCCCAUCCCAGUAUAUAGUAAUGUUUCUCUAAAUAGGGUCUGUAUCUAAAUGAAUAAGGUGAAAAUUGAGUACCCUCAAAGUACCCCAAGAGGGAGUCAUAUCAGAGACUGACAAGCGGUGGGUCUCUCAGGAAGCCCCAUACGGCCAGAUCUUGUUUUUCCAUGUUGGAACUGCAUGGCGUUUGUUAUUUUGAGCACAGGUGACGUGAACUGCUUGGGUGUGAGGCAUGUGAGAACUGAGACAUAGAACAGCAGCUGACCAUCUCCUAUUCUGUGCCCACUGUGAAGCAAGAAGUUAUUGAGUGGAGAUGCAAAGAAUGGAACUUGCACAGAUGGAGGCGUUUUGGAGUAGUGUAACUAACCAUACUUUGUAUUACGUGACCAGAACUGCUAUUUGAGAUUCUGGAAGCCAGUGAUGCAGUCUUGCUUGGGUAUUUACCUAGGGAGGGAGGGAGGGAGGGAGGAAUGGGUGGAUGGGUAGAUGGGUGGGUUGAUCAGCUGCUGUGUCAUAUCGGCACGGGGAAUAGAAUGGUGAACAAGGCAGAUCUGGUCUUUGCUCUCUCAUGGAACCUGCAUUCCAACUGGGGGCAAGGAAUGGUGGUUUAGACAAUGAGGAAAUCAUUACAAUGUGAGAUAAUCAUUCAGGUCUUCGUGAGCUAAGGCCAAACAAACAAAAAACACUUGCUUUGAUGGACUGAAUACUGUUAUUAGAAGUAAAUAUGGAAAAUGAACCAGACCAUGAAAAUGUGGAACAGAGCCUCUGUGCCAAGACGAGCGAAGAAGAGCUGAAUAAGUCUUUCAAUCUAGAAGCUUCACUUUCAAAAUUCUCUUACAUAGAUAUGGACAAGGAACUGGAGUUCAAAAAUGAUCUGAUUGAUGACAAGGAGUUUGAUAUUCCUCAAGUUGAUACUCCUCCAACACUGGAAAGCAUACUAAAUGAGACUGAUGAUGAAGAUGAGUCUUUUAUUCUUGAGGAUCCUACAUUGUUAAACAUUGAUACUAUUGAUUCUCACUCCUAUGAUACUUCAUCUGUGGCAAGCUCAGAUAGUGGUGACAGGACCAACUUAAAAAGGAAGAAGAAAUUACCUGAUUCUUUUUCACUUCAUGGAUCAGUUAUGCGCCAUUCACUUUUGAAGGGAAUUUCUGCCCAGAUAGUGUCUGCAGCUGACAAAGUAGAUGCUGGCUUGCCUACAGCAAUUGCAGUAUCCAGUCUGAUAGCAGUGGGUACAUCUCAUGGAUUGGCUUUAAUAUUUGGAAAAGAUCAGAAUCAAGCUUUGCGACUCUGUCUGGGUAGCACUAGUGUUGGAGGUCAGUAUGGCGCUAUCUCUGCCCUCAGUAUCAACAAUGAUUGCUCAAGACUUCUUUGUGGCUUUGCUAAAGGACAGAUCACCAUGUGGGAUUUGGCCAGUGGAAAACUUCUAAGAUCAAUAACAGAUGCUCAUCCUCCAGGAACAGCAAUAUUGCAUAUCAAGUUUACAGAUGAUCCAACUCUUGCAAUUUGCAACGACAGCGGAGGCUCUGUUUUUGAAUUGACAUUUAAGAGAGUGAUGGGAGUGAGAACCUGUGAAUCUAGAUGUCUGUUCAGUGGUUCCAAGGGUGAAGUCUGCUGUAUUGAGCCUCUGCAUUCUAAGCCUGAGUUGAAAGAUCAUCCCAUCACACAGUUUUCAUUAUUGGCCAUGGCAUCCUUGACAAAAAUACUGGUCAUUGGAUUGAAACCAUCCUUGAAAGUAUGGAUGACUUUUCCCUAUGGCCGGAUGGAUCCUUCCAGUGUGCCACUGCUGGCCUGGCACUUUGUAGCAGUACAAAAUUACGUGAAUCCCAUGCUUGCCUUCUGCAGAGGAGAUGUUGUUCAUUUUCUAUUGGUAAAGAGAGAUGAAUCUGGAGCAAUACAUGUUACUAAGCAAAAGCAUCUUCACCUAUACUAUGACCUCAUCAACUUUACCUGGAUAAAUUCACGCACAGUUGUGCUCUUAGACAGCGUAGAGAAGUUGCAUGUGAUUGAUCGGCAAACACAAGAGGAAUUGGAGACAGUGGAGAUCUCAGAAGUUCAGCUGGUCUACAAUAGCAGCCAUUUCAAAUCACUAGCCACUGGAGGAAAUGUUAGCCAGGCACUGGCUUUGGUUGGAGAGAAGGCUUGUUAUCAAUCCAUCAGUAGCUAUGGUGGUCAGAUCUUUUAUUUGGGGACAAAAUCUGUUUAUGUGAUGAUGCUGAGGAGCUGGAGAGAGAGAGUGGAUCAUCUCCUGAAACAAGAUUGUCUUACAGAAGCGUUGGCUCUUGCGUGGUCUUUCCAUGAAGGAAAAGCAAAAGCAGUAGUGGGAUUAUCAGGGGAUGCCAGUAAGCGAAAGGCUAUUGUUGCAGACCGGAUGGUAGAAAUCCUAUUCCAUUAUGCAGAUCGAGCUCUGAAAAAGUGCCCAGACCAAGGAAAAAUCCAAGUGAUGGAGCAGCAUUUUCAGGAUAUGGUGCCUGUCAUAGUUGAUUACUGCCUUCUGCUGCAGCGAAAGGAUCUUUUAUUUAGUCAGAUGUAUGAUAAAUUAAGUGAGAAUUCAGUGGCCAAAGGAGUAUUUUUGGAGUGCCUUGAGCCAUAUAUUUUAAGUGAUAAAUUGGUGGGAAUCACACCCCAAGUAAUGAAAGACUUGAUUGUUCAUUUCCAAGAUAAAAAAUUAAUGGAAAAUGUGGAAGCGCUCAUUGUACAUAUGGAUAUCACCAGCCUAGAUAUUCAGCAGGUAGUUCUCAUGUGUUGGGAAAAUCGUUUAUAUGAUGCUAUGAUCUAUGUCUACAACAGAGGCAUGAAUGAAUUUAUUAGUCCAAUGGAGAAACUUUUCAGAGUCAUUGCUCCUCCUCUGAAUGCAGGAAAAACACUAACAGAUGAACAAGUUGUUAUGGGCAAUAAGCUCCUUGUAUAUAUUAGCUGUUGUCUAGCAGGUCGUGCCUAUCCCCUUGGUGACAUCCCUGAAGAUCUGGUUCCCUUGGUUAAAAACCAGGUUUUUGAAUUUCUAAUUCGCCUGCAUUCAGCAGAGGCUUCUCCUGAGGAAGAAAUCUAUCCUUACAUUCGGACUUUGCUACAUUUUGACACAAGAGAAUUUCUAAAUGUAUUGGCACUGACUUUUGAAGAUUUUAAAAAUGACAAGCAAGCUGUGGAAUAUCAACAGCGAAUUGUGGAUAUUUUGUUGAAAGUUAUGGUGGAGAAUUCAGACUUUACCCCCUCACAAGUAGGAUGUCUCUUUACCUUCCUUGCUCGGCAGCUUGCAAAGCCUGACAACACCUUGUUUGUAAACAGAACACUUUUUGAUCAGGUCCUUGAAUUCCUUUGUAGUCCUGACGAUGACUCCCGACACUCUGAAAGACAGCAGGUCCUUUUAGAAUUGCUGCAGGCUGGAGGCAUAGUUCAAUUUGAAGAGAGUCGACUCAUCCGGAUGGCAGAAAAAGCUGAGUUCUAUCAAAUUUGUGAAUUUAUGUAUGAAAGAGAACACCAAUAUGAUAAAAUUAUUGAUUGCUACUUACGUGACCCUCUGCGAGAGGAAGAAGUCUUUAAUUACAUUCACAAUAUCUUAUCCAUUCCCGGACACAGUGCAGAGGAGAAGCAGUCUGUAUGGCAGAAAGCAAUGGAUCAUAUUGAGGAACUCGUGUCCCUGAAGCCUUGUAAAGCUGCGGAGCUGGUUGCCACCCACUUUUCUGGACAUAUUGAAACGGUCAUUAAAAAACUUCAGAACCAGGUUUUGCUUUUCAAAUUUUUGAGGAGUCUUCUUGACCCAAGGGAAGGUAUUCAUGUAAAUCAAGAAUUACUGCAAAUAUCUCCUUGUAUCACAGAGCAGUUCAUUGAGCUGUUGUGUCAGUUCAACCCAACCCAAGUUAUAGAGACUCUGCAAGUCCUUGAGUGCUACCGUCUGGAAGAAACUAUUCAGAUUACUCAGAAGUAUCAACUUCAUGAAGUCACCGCUUAUCUAUUGGAAAAGAAAGGAGAUAUUCAUGGUGCCUUCCUAAUAAUGUUAGAGAGACUACAAAGCAAACUUCAAGAGGUAACACAUCAAGGUGAAAAUACCAAAGAGGAUCCCUCAUUGAAGGAUGUUGAAGAUACUAUGGUGGAGACCAUUGCUCUUUGCCAGAGAAAUUCACAUAAUUUGAACCAGCAGCAACGUGAGGCACUUUGGUUUCCGUUAUUGGAGGCAAUGAUGGCCCCUCAGAAGCUGUCCAGUUCAGCCAUUCCUCAUCUACACUCUGAAGCUCUGAAGUCUUUGACCAUGCAAGUUUUAAAUAGCAUGGCAGCAUUUAUUGCCCUUCCAUCAAUCUUGCAAAGAAUCUUACAGGAUCCAGUUUAUGGAAAAGGAAAACUUGGAGAAAUCCAGGGACUUAUCUUGGGAAUGUUAGAUACCUUUAACUAUGAACAAACCCUGCUGGAAACAACAACCAGCCUUCUAAACCAAGAUCUCCAUUGGUCAUUGUGUAACCUGAGAGCUUCGGUCACCAGAGGACUGAAUCCCAAACAAGAUUACUGCUCUAUAUGUUUGCAGCAGUACAAGAGACGCCAAGAAAUGGCUGAUGAAAUAAUUGUCUUUAGCUGUGGCCAUUUGUAUCACUCAUUCUGCCUACAAAACAAAGAAUGCACUGUGGAAUUUGAGGGCCAAACAAGAUGGACAUGCUACAAAUGCAGUUCAAGUAACAAAGUAGGAAAACUCAGUGAAAAUUCAUCUGAAAUUAAAAAGGGAAGGAUAACCCCAUCACAGGUAAAAAUGUCUCCAUCGUAUCAUCAGUCCAAAGGGGAUCCCACUGCUAAAAAGGGAACCUCAGAACCUGUUCUGGAUCCACAGCAAAUCCAAGCAUUUGAUCAGCUUUGCCGUCUCUACCGAGGAAGCUCCAGGCUGGCUCUCCUCACGGAACUCUCCCAGAAUCGCAGCAGCGAGAGCUAUAGGCCAUUCAGUGGCUCGCAGAGUGCUCCUGCUUUCAACAGCAUCUUCCAGAAUGAGAACUUCCAGCUGCAGCUCAUUCCUCCACCUGUGACUGAGGAUUGAUGACUCCAUGGAGCCUGGCCCAGGAGAACCAGAGAUGAUCCCGAGGCAGCUGGGGAGAGGCCCCGCCUCUGGUGGGCUUGGCCUCCACCACCUCCCACGCUUCUGAGAAGAGGUUCCAAAUUGGGCUUCUGUGCCCAGAGCGUCCACAGCACCAUUCCCAGUGUAGACUCCCAGUCUUCUCCACAUUGCUGUCAUGGCGUCAGUUCACCAGACUCAUUGAUUUUGUUUUGCUUGUUAAGCAAAGGAAUGUCACAUACCUCUGUCCAGCUUUUUAGGAAAUACAUUUCGCCUAUUGCGACUUUUUCCAUUUACCCUGAAGCCUAGAAAGUAGGUGGAACUCACACAAAUGGCAUUCCAGAGUCUGCCAUACUCCGUCUCCUCCAGCUGCUGGAUAAUACAGAGGAACUUCAACUUCUACAGGGAACAGUGGUUGGCCAGGCUGCAGUAUAACUGAAGCAUGCCUUGGAGAGAGCAGACACUGUGGGGGCCAGGGCCAUCUCCCUUUAAUGUGUUCAUGUUAAAACCUAUUUGAGUGUAAGACUUGCCCUUUCUAACAAUAAAUGCUCCGUGUUUAAGUUCUGCAGGUCUC